AUUCAGUAUUGUGUAGUACAGAAAAGAUCACACAUGUAUAUGUCAGAAGUAGAUGCACAUGUUCUUUUGGCUUUUUUUCUUUGUUUUAUUCUUUUUUCAUUUUUUGUGUUUUUUGUUAGUUUGUUUUGAAUUUUUUUUCUUGAUGCAUAUGUUCCUUCAACUUAUUCAGUACUUCCAUGUGCAGGGCUCUGGACUAGACUUUCAGGAUCUAAGGCUGAAUCCUACACAGUCCUCCCUCUGGGAAAGUGAUGAAACCUGUGAGCUCUCCUAGCAACUCUGCAGUCUUCCUUCAAGGGCCUGUGCUUCCUUCAGAGACUCACACAAGAGGUUUAUCAUGAGAAGGACCGCACUAUUUCAUUUCACUCCUACAAGUUUUCAUUUACGUUACACAUUGAGAAAGUUAUGAGAAGCAACUGUCACUCUCUGGAGGUGGAGACUGCCGUGAUUCACAAAGACAAGAGGUAAUUUUCCUGUAAUCACAGGAUGACUCAGGAUGGAUCAUGAAGCCGCCCAGCUGGAGAAGCAGCAUGUGCACAAUGUGUACGAGAGCACAGCCCCUUACUUCAGCGACCUGCAGAGCAAAGCCUGGCCUCGUGUCCGCCAGUUCCUGCAAGAGCAGAAGCCAGGCAGCCUCAUCGCUGACAUAGGUUGUGGGACUGGAAAAUAUCUUAAAGUGAACAGCCAGGUACAUACCGUGGGCUGUGACUACUGUGGGCCACUGGUAGAGAUUGCCCGGAAUAGAGGAUGUGAAGCCAUGGUAUGUGACAACCUUAAUCUCCCCUUUAGGGAUGAGGGCUUCGAUGCCAUCAUCUCCAUAGGAGUCAUACAUCAUUUUUCUACAAAACAAAGAAGAAUCAGAGCAAUAAAAGAAAUGGCCAGGGUCUUAGUUCCCGGAGGCCAACUGAUGAUUUACGUUUGGGCAAUGGAACAAAAGAACCGUCGCUUUGAGAAGCAAGACGUGCUUGUUCCAUGGAACAGGGCCCUGUGUUCCCAGCUCUUCUCAGAGUCCAGCCAGUCUGGGAGGAAGAGGCAGUGUGGAUACCCAGAAAGAGGCCAUCCCUACCAUCCUCCUUGCUCUGAGUGUAGCUGUUCUGUUUGUUUUAAAGAGCAGGGUGGUUCAAAACGGUCCCACAGUGUGGGCUAUGAACCUGCUAUGGCAAGAACCUGUUUUGCAAAUAUUUCUAAGGAAGGCGAGGAAGAAUAUGGAUUUUACAGCACAUUAGGAAAAUCGUUUCGUUCCUGGUUUUUCUCCAGAUCUUUGGAUGAAUCGACUCUGAGGAAGCAAAUUGAAAGAGUAAGACCCUUGAAAAACACAGAAGUUUGGGCCAGUAGCACUGUAACAGUCCAGCCUUCCAGACACUCUAGUCUAGACUUUGAUCACCAAGAGCCAUUUUCAACAAAAGAGCAAAGUUUAGAUGAGGAAGUGUUUGUGGAAUCUUCUUCUGGAAAACACUUGGAGUGGCUGAGAGCACCAGGCACUCUGAAACAUUUAAAUGGAGACCAUCAAGGGGAAAUGAGGAGAAAUGGAGGGGGAAAUUUUCUGGAUAGCACUAAUACUGGUGUGAAUUGUGUGGAUGCAGGCAACAUAGAAGAUGAUAAUCCUUCUGCUAGUAAAAUAUUGAGAAGGAUUUCUGCAGUCGAUUCCACAGAUUUCAACCCAGAUGAUACAAUGUCUGUCGAAGAUCCACAGACUGAUGUUUUGGACUCCACAGCCUUUAUGCGCUACUACCAUGUGUUUCGAGAAGGGGAGCUCUGCAGUCUGCUCAAGGAGAAUGUGUCAGAGCUCCGUAUCCUGAGUUCUGGGAAUGAUCAUGGUAACUGGUGUAUCAUUGCAGAGAAAAAGGGAGGUUGUGAUUGAUUGGAUCCUUUUAGACAACUCCUCCAAAAGAUGAACCACAUUCUUUUCUCUUGGUUUGAUAUGGUUACCUGAAUUUGCAUUCAGUGUUAUUUGUUAAUCCAUUUACGCUUUGGUCUGCAGAGACUAUUAAUUAUUUGGUUGUUUUUGUUUUCAUGUUUGAAUAAGCACAGAUUCUGGCAUUGAAAGCACUUGACAAAGGGUAUUUGUGCUUAAAUGUUAAUAUAAAAGAUCUGAAGAAGCAACAGAAAGUACCCUUCAGUACACCUCAGACUUUUUUUUAACCCCAGAGAGAUAAAAUACAUGUAUAGUGUUUUUCAGUAUUACACAUUGAUUUAAAAAGAUUAUGCUGUUAAAUAAUCUUUUAAAACGGUAUUUUUAUAAAGUGAGGGGAUAAUUUCUGGUUCUCAGGUUAUAACUGAGAGCAGUGUGCAAGAUAAUAGGUAAAUUUGAUCCAUUGCACAGAUAUACUUUGAACCAUGUGAUGAGUUAUCUUGUUGCCAAGGCCUUGCUUCUACUUAAAGUUUUCAGAAAACUGAGUGACAGUGGAGAGAACCAAGAAGUUUUACAAGGACUUUACUAAAUUAUAAGCAAACUUGCUUCAAAAUAAGUUGACAUGUGAUAAUAAGGUUUUCAAUGUAGCCCAGGAGGUUUUUAAAGGCACUGUUAGGCUGAGCAUGGUGGCUCAUGCCUGUAAUCCCAGCACUUUGGGAGGCCAAGGCAGAAGCAUCACUUGAACCCAGGAGUUCAAGAAUAGCCUGGGCAACAUAGCAAGACCCCAUCUCUAUAAAAAUUAGCAAGAUGUGGUGGUGCAUGCCUGUCAUCCAAGCUACUCAAGAGACUGAGGCAGGAGGAUCACGUGAGCCCAGGAAUUCAAGGCUGCAGUGAACUAUGAUUGCAUCACUGCACUGCAGCCUGGGCAACAUAGCAAGACUCUGUCUCAAAAUAAUAAUAAUAAUAAUAAUAAAGGCAUUGUUAGCUUGUAAGGAGUGGAGUAUGUAGGUAGUAGGAGUUAUAUGCAAGUACCCAAGUGGUAUUCUUCCAAUCUUAUUAGAAGCAUGAAUAUUCAAGAUUGAUAUUACUAUUGCUUAUUAGCAAGAUUGUUAUCAAUCAUGCUUAUUAGAAGGAUGAAUAUCCAAGACCAAGAUUGACUAAUGAUGAGUCUGCAUCAAGAACUAGGCAUUUCUUCUGAGUUGACGGACUCUUUAGGAAAGGAGAAUCUAAGUGAAGCACUGAUUUUAGCUCUGAGAACAAACAAAUUAAGGUACAGCAUAGUUAGCCUUGGUAGAGGUAUGACUUGGAUUUGCUGUAUCCUUUAAAAUAGUAUCUGGGCAUUUAUUUUAUUGAAGGUGACUACAUUUUAUUAGUUAUAUUAGGAAUUUAGGUAGAAUCAACUUCUACUGAUUACAGGUUGAAUUUCUGUCACUUUGUAGAGAAACGAAUAGACUGGACACUGUGUGGUCACUGUUUAGAUUUGCCCAUGGGUCUGUUUAAAUCUAUGUCAUGGAUCCUGAGACACAAAUAUAAUUAAGACAGGUCUAGAGACAGGAGAAGCAGAAAUAAGUUGACCCAGGAGUACAGUCUCAAGUAGUUCAUUAAUGAGAAAAUUGACAUCUGACAAGAGUCUUUUUACUUUAUGCUGGAUGAAAAUCCAAAUCUUGUUUUAUUUUUUCCACUAAAAGUGACUAAAAUAAUAACGAAUUUCAUUUGUUCUUGGGUUCUUUUUUCCUUUAAUGAUUGUGCUAUAACUUAAAAUAAUGAUGUUACCUUUGAACAAACUUAAAGAAAUAUUUUUAAAGCGUAUCUGAAAACGAUUGAUGUUUAUAACUCUCUUUUGGCUUCAAAAUAAGAUUGUGUUAUCACCAUUUUGGUAGAUGAGGUUGUCUGGUGAAAAUGAUGCAUAUGAGUUGUACUGUUCAGUGUACAUCCUGCAGUAGUGGAUGAUUGAAAACAUAUAUAAGUGGAGUAUAAAUUAAAAAUUAAUUUGGUUUCUUCUAUUUCUUUUUUUUUUUUUUUUUUUUUUUGAGACAGAGUCUCGCUCUGUCGCCCAGGCUGGAGUGCACUGGCGCGAUCUCGGCUCACUGUAAGCUCCGCCCUCCGGGUUCACGCCAUCCUCCUGCCUCAGCCUCCCAAGUAGCUGGGACUACUGGCACCCACCACGACGCCCGGCUGUUUUUUUGUAUUUUUAGGAGAGACGGGGUUUCACCGUGUUAGCCAGGAUGGUCUCGAUCUCCUGACGUCGUGAUCCACCCGCCUCGGCCCCCCACAGUGCUGGGAUUACAGGCGUGAGCCACCGAGCCCGGCCUGUUCCUUUUAUUUCUUAAUUCAGGACACUAAACCAUGACUGCAAGGGAUUUCCUUGGUAAAAAGAAAAGAUUCUCAGAGUCAAAAUGUUCUUACAACUCGGGCUUGACGGCCUUUGAAUUAUGAAUGGAUUGUUCCUCUCUCUGAAGCCUAUUGUCACAUGGGUUUUUAAUCCUGGCCUUGCUGCUAGAAAUCUGUGCUUGAAGUCCUCUCUUUCUGCUGGUAGCCUACCAGUUAAAAGUCAAGACUUGGUGGAACUCAGUUUACCAGACUCUUUAGCCUUUGAGCUAAACUGUCUGAGCAACCUCUUAGAUGUGCACACACCACUUUGUAUGAAAGGGUUCUCUAGAACGGUUCUUUGGAGAGAAAUAUUUUCAUGUACGUUUGACAGGGGUGUAAAUAAAGCAUGCUGACUAAUAAGUCUUUUACUCUUCAUCUAAUGAACAUAAGAAUCUAUGCAUCCAGAUAUUAUUUUGUAUACAAAUAUUUAAUUUGGUGAUUGAUAAUCUCUCUUUGGGGUAGUCACAUGGAAAGCUCUUUUAAAUUUAACUUCCGCCUUUGGAUUUUUUUUAAAAAGCCAUUGAAGAGCAAAACUAAUGUAAACGUCUUGAUCAUUUAAAAAGCUUGCUUGUCCUCGAAAGGAAACACAGGUCAUCAGUGAGUAUAAACGUAGACAGUUGAUUUGUGAAUGCUGUCGGCCUCAACUUGCUUGAUGAUAGAUUCUACUGACCUAGCUGGAGUAAUCUGAUCACUUACUUCCUUAUUAAUACUAGAUCACACAGUAUCUUUCUUAUUCCUUCUUCUUUACUUACUGGCAUCAGCACAGAGUCCCACUAUCUGAAAUAGAAGGGAGAGUUUGGGGGUUUAUUGGAGGAGUCUUAAAAACUUGGUUGGCAGCUGGGUACGAUGACUCACACCUGUACUCCCAGCACUUCAGGAAGCUGAGGUGGGUGGAUCAGCUGAGGUCAGGAGUUUGAGACCAGCCUGACCAACAUGGUGAAACCCCGUCUUUAUUAAAUACAAAAAAUUAGCCAGGUUGGUGGCGCAUGCCUGUAAUCCCAGCUACUUGGGAGGCUGAGGCAGGAGAAUCGCUUGAACCUGGGAGGCGGAGGUUGCAGUGAGCCGAGAUUGUGCCAUUGCACUCCAACCUGGGCAACAAGAGUGAAACUCCAUCUCCAACAAAACAAAACUUUGCUGGCUUCCUGAUGCCUCACUGUCUAUUUGAGGAAUUCCACAGAAUCUUCAAAGGAUUUGGGGGAAAGCGCAUUAACAUGGACAAAGGAUGGAAUCAAAAUAAUGUUAUAGUGAGAAUCAUUCAAGCACCUAUUUAAAUUUUUUCCAAUUGCCAGUAUAGUGAUGAUAUGACACCAGCAUAUCAAAGUAACUAACAAACUAGCUACACAAACGUCUUGGAGUUUGGUUUCGUUCUCUUUUCUCAUCAUAGAUCUCCGUGCAGAAUAGUGCUAAUUCUUAUUUCUCGUUUGCCUUUCUAUUUCCUUCCAAAUUCUACAUGCCAGUAAUUCCUCUGUCUUUUAAGUGACCAUCAAUUCAAUAGGCAAAAAUUUGGAGUAAUCCAGAGAAAAAACCAUCCAAAUAUAAACCAGCUAGGAACAUGAAUGCCCCUGAUUAUUAAUGGCCAAAAAAAAAGCACUGGUGGAUUUUAAAUUAAAUUAAUACAUAUAUACGAGUUUGGAGGAGAACAGAAGUUCUAACUCAGUACUUGAACUUGGUGGGGGAGGGCACAGGUUAAAUAUGAGCUGUGAGCCCCCAGUUUUGGAGGAAGGAGGAAAUGGGAACCAACCACCAGACAAGCAGCUGCAGUCUAAGAAAAACAAAUUAGGGCAGGCCUCAGCAUCUCUUUCCUAUUACAUAGAAAAUCUGAAAUGAGAAUAGCUGUGAACUUUUCUAAAUAUGCAACAUUCAACUAUCGCAAGGACAAAAAACCAAACACCGCAUGUUCUCACUCAUAGGUGGGAAUUGAACAAUGAGAACACAUGGACACAGGAAGGGGAACAUCACACACUGGGACCUGUUGUGACCCCGCUGAGGGAGUUCCUCUUGCCCUCUACCCCCGGGGCUUGUAUAUAGAUUAUAAAUAUAUAAGGGGGAAAGGGGUGGGGGGGAGGGGUUGUGCGGCUGGGGCCUCACUUCCCCUCCUUCCCCUUCUCCUGGUCCCCUGUCCCAGGGGCUGUUUGUUAAAAAAGAGUAAUAAAGGAUUUUUGUUUUUAAAAAAAGCAACGUUCAUUAAUUUAUAUGCAGUCCUCACCACAGCCCUCCAAGAUAAGUACACUUAUUGUUCCCAUUUUGCAGAUGAGGAAAACUGAGGCAGAAAGAAAUUAAAUUGCUUAAGGUUACACACAUAGUAGGUAUCACACAUUUAGUUAGAGGCAGAGCUGGGAUUCAAACCCAGGUCUGGCUCCUAGUCUCUGCUCUUAACCACAACACCAUAUACUCCCACCCCUGGGCCCAGCUCAUGUGCUUGGCGGAGUAUUAGAGCCUUUCAAGGUAAGUGUGAUUAUCCCCUUUCCAAAUGAGCUUUGGAAAAGUUUAAGCAAAGAUUACACAGCUAGACAAUAAUUCAAUAGUAGUCUCUUACAUAUUUUCCCUUUUAUCUUUUUUUCAUUUGUGAAUCUGUUUCGAUUUGAUUUGAAUUAAAAAAUAGUUCUUGGUUGCAAAAUAUUCUGGGACCACUUUUCUCCAACUCUUCAACCUUUCAACAAUUAUAUUAUUGUUUUCCCAUUUUAUAAGUAAGGCAACUGAGGACUAUUCAGAUAUUUCAUUCACUCCAUUUGUUUACUAAGCCCUGCUGUGUGCUGGAUACACAGUCUGCUGUGUGCUGGAUACAUAUGAUACAAGGUAAUGACUAUCUGGCAUCUUGAAGGUACCCAGAAUAUUAGAAUUAACUGACCCACAGGUGCCAAGCUGAAACAUUCUUCGUAUUCCCUGUGUGCCUAUUACCAAGUUAUAUUGUUUAGUUUGAGGAAAACAACAAACAACCCUCCCUUAGAGAAUCAUGAUGCAUAUUAGCAUAUUUAAGGAGUACCCUAAAGCUUGGACUUAAUCUAGCUUACCCUAGACGUAUUAACAUCCUAUAGCGCACGUGUUCUGUGGGAUAUAUUUCAGAAAAUAAUAUGUCUUACAGAAUAAAUGCAGACUCCUUUGGAUGGCAUUCAGGCCCUUCAUAAACUAACUCUGAAUUAUUUUUCAGUCUCAUUUCCUGCAGUUGCACCCGAUUUUUUCUGUUCUGCAAUCUGCUAUUUUAGACAAAGCUUUCAUAAGAAAUUACAUAAUGACAAGUAAUUCCCACAUUCCCUAGAUAUAUACUUGGAUUUCAAAUGCCAUAAUUGUAAUCUUUCUCCAAAGAAAAAUGCACGAUACAGGCUUCAUUCCAUCAAGAGGCAUAUGAGGUAAGCGUUAUUAUACACCCGUCCAGCAGAUGGGAAAACCACGGAAGUGGGAGGGAAUCAAGAAGCAUUAACAGACCCUCCACCAACCGUAAUGCUUAACUCCUCUUGUUCCAAUCUUAACUCAAAAUUAUGAUUAUUUUGAUUAUUUAAUGAUUGUUUUGAUAGUAUAAACUCCAUAUCUGCAACCUCAGUUAUCUACAACACUGAAGUGCAAACAUUUAAAAAGAUCUCUCACCAAACAAGGAUUGAAAUUGUAUUGCAAAUGAAAGAGCUCAGCAUGAGAGCACAAUCAGAAACUGAAGAGAGUUGAUCAAAGAGAAGAUUCUAGCUGAAUUGUUCUAUUUUUAAUUCCCCAGGGAUCCUACGGUCUAUGACACAUUAACAGGGGUGUGAAUCAUUUCAGUUACAUCACAUACUCUGUCCUCUUGCGGUGCGGGUCUUCCCCAGUUGAUUAUACACAGAUAAUCAAUGACUUUAUUUGGGAGGGAUUGGAGCUAUAGAAUAAUCUAUCUUACCAAUCUGAUGGACCAUUUGUAAGAGCUGUUUGUCAAAUUGGAUCUUCAUUUGACAAAUAAAUACUAGAGCUGCAGAAAGUAAAGUUUACUCCAACCCAAUUAAUCAUUAAUACAUCCACAGGAAAAAUACAUUUUCUCCACAUGGAAUAUUGAUUUUUCUAUGAAUAUUACCUCCACAUUGAAAAACGAGUGAGUCACUGCAGUUAAGCCAGUGUACCUUGAUGUUGAAUUCCCUGAAGAAGGUACAAUUAUAUUUACAUUCCCUUAGCAAGAAUUUGGCUAAGUGAUAAGCACUUUUCUCUUUUCUUUUCUUUUUUUUUUUUUUUUUUUGAGACAGUGUCUCACUCUGUCACCCAGGCUGGAGGGCAGUAGUGCAGUCUCAGCUCAUUGCAACCUCUGCCUCCCAGGUUUAAGCAAUUCUCGUGCCUCAGCCUCCUGAAUAGCUGGGAUUACAGGAACAUGCCACCACUCCUGGCUAAUUUUUGUAUUUUUUUUUAAGUAAAGACAAACUUUCACCAUGUUGGCCAGGCUGGUCUUGAACUCCUGACCUCUUACGAGCUAAUCAUACCACUUCUAACUAGAUUUUCUAUUAAUGUACAAGGAGGGACUCCACUACUAAAGUUUGUUUUACUUCUCUGGUUAUUUACACAAAACGCUGGCAAUACAUUAAGGCUCACUAAUGUGGACCUAAGUGAGUUUCUGAGAGGCUUUGAAUAUGUAUGUGCAAACUGUCCUAUUUUCUUUAUAUGCUCUCUUAAAUAUGUAUGUCUGUAAAUAUAUAUAUAACACACAUAUAUAUAUAUUCCUAGACAUCUAGUGUUUGCUGUCAUUAGUGACCAAGAAAAAGUAGUUCUUUUGUGCACGCGUGAAUACAUCAAAUUAGCAAUUACCAUAGAAAUGUAUUUCAUUGAAUAAAUAGCUUUUGUUUGUUUGUUUGUUUGUUUGUUUCAGGGAAAUUUAGAACAAUUAUUAGAUGUUAUUGUGCCUCUUCUCGUGUUGAUACGUGUAUUUGGGUCAAAAGUGCAAAAACUUUUUUCUACAAUGUACAGUUAUUUUGACUUUUCCCAGGGGAAGCUAGCAAUAGUUUUAAAAGCACAAAGUGAUGUAAAAUAUUUUGACUUUUAUAAUAAUGCGAAGUAGUUUUAUUUGCAUUAAUCAAUAAUGUUCAGGAUCUUUUUGUAGUAAGUAUAUUUUAAAUGGUGUAAUUUGUGUGUUUAUGAUAUGUAUUCAAUUAUUUAAGUUAAGUAUCAGUGUAUUUUUAAAAAGUGUUCCCAGGUGAACAAAAGUUUGCUUUUCUUCACCAUUCUGUACAGGACAAGCAUUAUUCAGUUCACAUAGUCAGCUCUCACUACACUUCAACAGAACGGGGCAAGUUCGUAUUUGAAUUCUGUUAUAUUUAUCUAAGGGAAGCAAAAUUAACCUUUUAAUAAUAGAUUAUCUUUAAUGGUUAUUAAAAGAAUGUUAUUGACCAAAAAGACAUAUUUUGAGAUUAAUAAAGAUGUAUUAGAUUAUCCAAAA